ACUGGGAAUUACAAUUCAACAUGAGAUUUGGGUGGGGACACAGAGCCAAACCAUAUCACAUGUCUAGUGGAAUAGCUUUGGACUAGGACCUCUAUUUUUCUGUAACAAUCCAUGUUACUUUAGCCAAUGAGUCUAAGCCAAUUAUAUCAGUGUAAUAUACAUCAAUUUUCUCAUCCAUAAAAUGGAGCCACCCAUUUAUUCUCUACUGCAUAUGAUGAUGAGAUGAAUGUGAGAUAACAUGCAAGAGAAUUCUUUGCAAAAUGCUAUAAAACUGUAAGAUAUUAUUAACCUGACAUGCUGUAAAAAUGUAUGACCAAAUGUUUGUAAAAUUAUUCCAUGUGAAAAUGACAAGGAAUUGUCUUUUAAGGUUGAUGGGGCUAGGCACCAUGGCUCACACCUGUAAUACCAGCACUUCGGGAGGCCAAAGCAGGAGGCUCACUUGAGGCCAGGAAUUCAAGACCAAACCUGGGUAACAUUGUAAGACCACAUCACUAUAAAAAAUUAAAAACUUAGCCAGGUGUGGUAGCGUGGCACCUGUAGACCUAGCUACUGGGGAGGCUGAGCUGGAAAGAUUGCUUGAGGCCAGAAGUUUGAGGCUGCAUUGAGUCAUAAUUGCACCACUGCACUCCAGCCUGGGUGACAGAGCAAGACCCUGUCCCUACAAACAAAUAAUAAUAAUAAUAAUAAAAGAUUGACGUAAGGUGACCAAUCAGGGAUAGUUAUAGUCCAGGGAUAGUCUAGAGCUGGUAUGAGAAUGAAUACAGAAAAAUGAUAAAAUUAUUAAAAUAAUGAGAUUUUUCAUAAAAAGGGAUAUUUUAGCUCAGACUGUCCAUUUCCUUUUCUUUUUUUUUCCUUUCCAACUUUUAUUUGAGGUUUGGGGGUACACACGCAGGUUUGUUUGGGAAAAUUGCAUGUCGCAGGGGUUAGGUGUACAGAUUAUUUCAUCACCCAGGUAAUAACCAUAGCACCUGAUACAUAGUUUUUUGAUCCUUACCCUCCUCCCGCCCUCCACCCUCAAGUAGGCCCUGGUCAGACUGUCCAUUUUCUAAUAUACCUUUGAAAGAGCUAUAAGAAUAAAGAUGUGCAUCUUUGCAAAGUUAAUAACCAGUCAAUAUACUUGUAUUUUUCUAUCAUUCUCUUUAUUACAUUUUAGCAGUAGUUUCUCUGCAUUUUAUUUAUUUUUUUUUUUUGGUGUUUAUAUUGUGUUUACUUACUUUUUUUUUUAGUUUUAUUUUUAACUGACACAUAAUAGUUAUACAUAUUAUCUAUGGGGUACAGUGUGAUAUUCCACUACAUGUAUACAUUGCAUAAUGAUCAACUCAGGGUAAUUAGCAUACUCAUCAUCUCAAGCAUUUUUCUUUUCUUUGUGGUGAGAACAUUCAAAAUUGUCUCUUCUAGCUGAUUUGAAAUAUACAACACAUUAUUGUUAAAUAUAUCAUUCUGCUGUGCCAUACAGCAGGUGUCCCCAACUACCGGGCUGCAAACUGGUACCAGCCUGUGGCCUGUUAGGAACUGAGCUGCACUGUAGGAGGUGAGUGUCAGCGAGCAUUCCCACCUGAGCUCUGCCCCUGUCAGAUCAGCAGCCGCAUUCGAUUCUCACAGGAGCACAAACCCUAUGGUGAACCGCACAUGGGAGGGAUCUAGGUUGCAUGCUCCUUCUGUGAACCUAACUAAUGCCGGAUGAUCUGAGAUGGAACAGUUUCAUCCUGAAACCAUCCCCCCUCAAAAUCCGUGGAAAAAUUGUCUUGCACAAAACAGGUCUUUGGUGCCAAAAAGGUUGAGACUACUGCGUUAGUGUACCAGAACUUAUUCCUCUCAUCUAACUAUAACCUAGUACCUACUAACCAACUUCUCCUACUCCUGCCACUCCUCCCCACCUUUCACCUGACUCUGCUAACCAGUAUUCUAGUCUCUACUUCUAUGUGAUCAACUUUUUAAAAUUCCACAUAUAAGUGAGAUCAUGUCGUAUUUGCCUUUUGUUUCUGGCUUUUCUUGCUUAACAUAAUGUCCUCCAGGUUCAUCCAUGUUGUUGCAAAUGACAGGAUUUCAUUCUUUUUGUUGAGGUCUUAUCCAAAAAAUCCUUGCCUGGACCAAUGUCAUGAAGUGUUUCCACUAUGUUUUUUUUCUAGCAGUUUCAUCAUCUCAGGUUUUACAUGGCAGUCUUUAUUUUGAGUUGAUGUUUGUUUGUUUGUUUGUUUGUUUGUUUGUUUUGAGACGGAGUCUUGCUCUGUUGCCCAGGCUGGAGUGCAGUGGUUUUAUCUCGGCUCACUGCAACCUCCGCAUCUCAGAUUCAGGUGAUUGUCCUGCCUCAGCCUCCCAAGUAGCUGGGAUUACAGGCGCCCACCACCACGCCCGGCUAAUUUUUGUGCUUUUAGUAGAGAUGGGGUUUCACCACAUUGGCCAGGCUGGUCUCAAACUCCUGACCUCAAGUGAUCUGCCUGCCUCGGCCUGCCAAAGUUCUGGGAUUACAGGCAUGAGCCACUGCAUCCGGCCUUGAGUUGAUUUUUGUAUAUGGUGAGAAAGAGGGGUCUAGUUUCAUUCUUCCACAUGUGGAUAUUCAGUUUUCCCAUCACCGUGAUUCUCUGCAUUUUAAAUUCUGUAAUCAUCCUGUGCCACUACCAUGGUGAAAACACAAAUAUUUAUAAUUCACUGAAUUCUCUGCCAGCCUGGAGGCUUUUGUCCUGGAAGUAUAUACUAAUUUUUUUUUGACAUUUUGGUAAUUGACUUUUGUCAAUACAAAUCUGUAAUUGAAGGAACAGUUCAGUCUAUCCACUGAAUUGUUCCUAGCCCGUCACUCAGUGACACUAGAUUGGAAAUACAGAAAGGCAUUUAAUUCUUUCUGCACUAGACUGGAAAUACAGAAAGGCAGUUAAUUCUUUCUGAGUCUUGAAACAUGAAAGUAAAUUAAAAAAAAAAACCUUUCAGUCUGGGAAUUGUGUUGAAAUCCAUAAACAUCUGAAACUUAGUGACUCAGAUUGUUAGUCACAGAGUCACUGGUUAGAAUCUGGAUGAAAUCCACUGUGGACAAAGGCCAGUAAUAAUGAUGAUGAUAUUUUGCUUUUCCAUAGUGCCGAACAAAACUCUUUACAAAUGUUACAAGUACAAAAGAAAGAGUAGCAAGACAUUUUUUCUGCAAGUGCUCAGGCUAAGUAAGACUCUUGCUAACUUUGAAGUAGUUUAUUUUUCCCUCUACAUAAAUACAAAAGAAAUGUAGUGGCAAAUAAUUGCAACAAAACCCAACUUAAGCAAAGGCCUCAUUAGUAUUCAAUUAGCAUAGUAACCCGUCUUUCCCGGUCUCUUGUUUGAAGCAGACUGGAUCCAAUGUGUAGUCUUGGAGUAAAGAAAAUAAUAUCUCCAGAGUAGGUCUUACAAAUAAAGCCAAGGCUACACUCAAUUGUGUUUUGUAUUAUUACACUUUCGUUAGUAAUUCACCUUCCACUGAAGAACACACAGAGGGUAGAUCUAAGUUUGUUCUCUUGCAAUAAUGUCAGACCUGAGGAAUAUCAGCAGUAAGCGCUGGGCAGUUUCAGAGAUAUCCUCCCACUAUCUCCCCUUCUGACCGGAACAGGAAUUGGAUAGCUUCAGAGCAAAAGAAUAAUGUGUCCAUGUGUUCCUCCAGAUCUCUGAGUCCUGGCAGUCGACCUCAACUCUCUUGGCCACCAUAAAGCAGUCAUUGAAAGGACACAGCUGCAGGAACUAGGGACUAAGCAGUAAAUAAAUCCACAGGGCUGGAGGCAGAAGUUACGUACAUGACCCUAAAACAAUACUCUGUGGUUAUGAACAAACUGAUUAGCAUCUGAGGGUCCUGUAGCAGCUUAUGCAAAAUUAAUUGGUGCCUCAGCCAGUGCUGAGUUUCUAAAGGAAAGAUGUCCACUUCAAAAACAAAAACAAAAAAAGGGGGGCCUCCUUAGUCAGCAGCAACUUUGCCUGGUGUCCUGGGGAGACGAUCAGCUAGAAUGGGAAUGGAGCUGUUUAUUCUCUUAGCUGUACAUGGAUUCUCUUCAGAUCAGAGCUGAUGUAUAACAGCCACUGGCAAUAUCCCAAGACAUGAUCCAGUGAUUGCCAGGUUAUGGGUUGCAUCUUAGAGUUAAGGUGAGAGGAGCUUGGGAAAGAGGUUGAGAGAUGUGGCUUGAGAGUGGGAGAGAUGGAGAAAGUAAAAGAAAUUGGACACUGAUCUACAUAGAGCAACACUUCCCUAAUUGGUUUUGGCUCCAACUCAGGCAGACUCAGCUUUAAAACCAGACUCCACCACCUACCACCUGAUUUUGACCACUCCACGUUUUGCAAAGAUCGGUUUUGCCUCAGAGUCAACAAACUCUUCAGAUUGGUUCCGGUGUGUCCUAUGUUUACAAGUCAGUGGAAAUUAAGCACAACACAUAUAAAUUGAAAAGUCAAAUAAGGAAAUGAAUUACCUCCCUUGACGGCUCUAAUUUUACUUGGCUAAAGCCAAUUUUUAGGUUGGCUUGGGCAGAAAAGUGAAAAGAGAAUGCUCCACUUUAACCGAUGUCAUCAUCUGAAAAAGAUAACACAGAAAUGUUUUUCUAGUAUACAUGUUAAAACGGAUAAACAUGCACAGCGAUUUCUUUCAAGAACCUUUGCACUUGCGGAAUUGAGGAAGUCAUGGUAUUCAACCCACUCUCUUGUUGGAGACAAAAAUAUUAUCCUGAUGGGACCUCCUGGUGCUGGGAAAACAACAGUAGGCAGAAUAAUAGGUCAGAAACUAGGUUGUUGUGUCAUAGAUGUGGAUGAUGAUAUCCUUGAAAAAACCUGGAAUAUGAGUGUGUCUGAAAAAUUACAGGAUGUUGGUAAUGAGCAAUUUUUAGAAGAGGAAGGAAAAGCUGUGUUAAACUUCUCUGCAUCUGGAAGUGUGAUUUCCCUUACUGGGUCCAAUCCAAUGCAUGAUGCUAGCAUGUGGCAUCUGAAGAAAAAUGGAAUAAUUGUAUACCUGGAUGUACCUCUACUAGAUCUAAUUUGUCGUCUAAAAUUAAUGAAGACAGAUAGGAUUGUAGGUCAGAAUUCUGGAACAUCUAUGAAAGACUUACUUAAAUUUAGAAGACAGUAUUAUAAGAAGUGGUAUGAUGCUCGUGUUUUCUGUGAAAGUGGGGCUUCCCCAGAGGAGGUAGCUGACAAAGUGCUGAAUGCAAUUAAAAGAUACCAAGAUGUGGACUCGGAAACAUUCAUUUCAACAAGACACGUUUGGCCUGAAGACUGUGAACAGAAGGUUUCAGCAAAAUUCUUUAGUGAAGCUGUAAUUGAGGGGUUGGCUUCUGAUGGUGGCCUCUUUGUUCCUGCAAAGGAGUUUCCAAAAUUAAGCUGCGGGGAGUGGAAAAGCCUAGUAGGAGCAACCUACGUAGAAAGAGCACAGAUACUGUUGGAAAGAUGUAUCCAUCCUGCAGACAUACCUGCUGCCAGGUUGGGAGAAAUGAUUGAAACUGCUUAUGGGGAAAACUUUGCCUGCUCAAAAAUUGCUCCUGUCAGGCACCUUUCAGGCAACCAGUUCAUCCUGGAGUUGUUUCAUGGACCAACAGGAUCAUUUAAAGAUUUGUCUUUACAGCUUAUGCCUCAUAUUUUUGCACACUGUAUCCCACCAAGUUGCAAUUAUAUGAUACUUGUAGCUACUUCAGGAGACACAGGGAGUGCAGUCUUAAAUGGUUUUAGUCGUCUAAAUAAGAAUGAUAAGCAAAGGAUAGCUGUGGUUGCAUUUUUUCCUGAGAAUGGAGUAAGUGAUUUUCAAAAAGCACAAAUAAUUGGCAGUCAGAGAGAAAAUGGAUGGGCAGUGGGUGUUGAGUCAGAUUUUGAUUUUUGCCAGACAGCUAUAAAAAGAAUUUUUAAUGAUUCUGAUUUUACUGGCUUUCUUACUGUGGAAUAUGGAACAAUCUUAAGUUCGGCUAACUCCAUAAACUGGGGCCGACUACUUCCGCAGGUAGUUUAUCAUGCUUCCGCAUAUCUUGAUCUUGUUAGUCAAGGAUUUAUUUCUUUUGGAAGCCCAGUCGAUGUCUGUAUUCCCACAGGAAACUUUGGUAACAUUUUAGCAGCAGUGUAUGCCAAAAUGAUGGGAAUCCCGAUUCGAAAAUUUAUCUGUGCCUCUAAUCAGAACCAUGUUUUGACUGAUUUUAUAAAAACAGGACAUUAUGAUCUAAGGGAAAGAAAACUAGCACAAACCUUUUCACCGUCAAUAGAUAUUCUCAAAUCUUCAAACCUAGAACGACAUUUACACUUGAUGGCUAAUAAAGAUGGACAGCUAAUGACAGAAUUAUUUAAUCGAUUAGAAAGUCAGCAUCAUUUCCAGAUAGAAAAGGCUCUAGUUGAGAAACUUCAGCAGGAUUUUGUAGCUGACUGGUGCUCUGAGGGAGAGUGCCUAGCAGCUAUUAACUCCACCUAUAAUACUUCAGGGUAUAUUUUGGAUCCACACACUGCUGUUGCAAAAGUGGUUGCAGAUAGGGUGCAAGACAAAACUUGCCCUGUGAUUAUCUCAUCUACAGCCCAUUACUCAAAGUUUGCACCUGCUAUCAUGCAGGCUUUAAAGAUUAAAGAAAUCAAUGAGACUUCAUCAAGUCAGCUCUAUUUGCUGGGUUCAUACAAUGCAUUACCUCCACUGCAUGAGGCUUUAUUAGAGAGAACAAAACAGCAAGAGAAGAUGGAGUACCAGGUCUGUGCAGCUGAUAUGAAUGUCUUGAAGAGUCAUGUGGAACAACUUGUCCAAAAUCAAUUCAUAUGAAAGCUUUCAGAGUAAAUUUUUUUUUCUAGCUAUAAGCAUGCAAUAAUAAAUCUCAAACACUGAUUUGGAGUACAGUAGCAUUUUGUCUUUUAUGUAAAUAUCUCUAUAUCUGUUUGGAAUUUCAAAAGUCUGAUCUCUAGGGCUGACAUGAGAACUCCAUGUCACCUCCUCAGAUCUUUAAUCUGGAAGUGACAAAAGGUAACACAGUGCACGGACCUUUGAGCUAUCAUACUUUUGCCUUCUGCUCAUGAGGGGUGUAUCAAUUUCCACUCCCACACCCUCACUGUUAUGUGGACCAAAAUGUCUGGUAUACUAUUUGGCGAUUAAAAUAUUUAAGCCCAGUUUUCAGGUACUACAUCUGUAACUAGUGAAUACUCUGUUGAUUAGAAAGUUAAUUUACCACUCAAAAUGGCUAACUUGAAUGGAGGAAGUAGUAAACUCUUCUAUUAGGAUUUGGGCCAGUGUUUUUUGUUUGUUUUUUGGUGCAGUUUCAGCUCACUGCAACCUCCGCCUCCCAGGUUCAAGUGAUUCUCCUGCCUCAGCCUCCCAGGUAGCUGGGAUUACAGGCAUGCAACACCACACAUGGCUAAUUUUUUUAUUUUUAAUAGAGAUGAGGUUUCGCCAUGUUUUCCAGGCUGAUCUUGAACCUCUGACCUCAGGUGAUCCAUCCACCUCGGCCUCCCAAAGUGCUAGGAUUACAGGCGUGAGCCUCUGCACCUGGCUAGGGCCAGUGUUUUUAACCCUCCUCAAAUUCCAUUUUGGACUACAACUAAUGUGUAUCUCACACUGUCCAAAUUAAAGAUGUACUCUGUCCUUCACUCUCCUUUGGAUGUGUACGGUUAGGGUGACGAUGUUUGAAAAUCAACACAUAACUGAAAUCCAGGAUGAAACAGUAAGCAGAACUACUUAGAAGUGAAUACAGAAAUGAUCUAUUUCAAGAGGAAGGUUUUCCAAAAUUAAGAGUACUUGAGUAGUCUCAAUAGGAGUGUAUUUGUAGACAGCAGUUUCCCUAUAUUAUUUGGAGUCAAUUCUUACGUAAUUUGUUGUUUAUUUCUUCAGUGAACAUUGUCUUUUUCUGGCAGCUGAAACUGCACACAACUGAUACACAUAUUUAAUUUGUAUUCCUUUGUAGUAAUACAUUUUAACCAUGAUUUAUGUUUGUGAAUUUACUGGAUGUUUUCUUUCUGAAUUAAAGAUUGUCAAGACCAA